AGACGCGCGCAAACCCGGAAGCAGAUCGCGUGGAGUGAAGGUCCCUCAGCGGCGCGAUUGACAUCUAAAGACUCUUGGUACAUGAGGAAGAAACCCGGAAAAGGAAAGCAGAGGAGUCAGGGAUGGCUCUUCCUCAGGGUCUAUUGACAUUCAGGGAUGUGGCCAUAGAAUUCUCUCAGGAGGAGUGGAAAUGCCUGGACCCUGCUCAGAGGACUCUAUACAGGGACGUGAUGCUGGAGAAUUAUAGGAACCUGGUCUCCCUGGGUAUCUCUUCCAAAUGCACAAUGAAGGAGUUCUCAUCAACAGCACAAGGCAAUACAGAAGUGAUCCACACAGGGACAUUGCAAAGACAUGAACGUCAUCACAUUGGAGAUUUUUCCUUCCAGGAAAUUGAGAAAGAUAUUCAUAACUUUGAGUUUCAGUGGCAAGAAGAUGAAAGAAAUGGCCAUGAAGCACCCAUGACAAAAAUCAAAAAAUUGAUGGGUAGUACAGAGCAAUAUGAUCACAGGCAUGCUGGAAACAAGCCUAUUAAAUAUCAGCUUGGAUCAAGCUUUCAUUCACAUCUGUCUGAACUCCACAUAUUUCAGCCCAAAGGGAAAAUUAAUAAUCAAGUGGAGAAGUCUAUCAACGAUGCUUCCUCGGUUUCAACAGCCCAAAGAAUUUCUUGUAGGCCCAAAACCCAUAUAUCUAAUAACUAUGGGGAUAAUUUUCUGAAUUAUUCAUUACUCACACAAAGACAGGAAGUACGCAUGAGAGAAAAAUCUUUCCAAUGUAUUGAGAGUGGCAAAGCCUUUAAUUAUAGCUCACUCUUAAGGAAACAUCAGAUUAUUCAUCUAGGAGAGAAACAAUAUAAAUGUGAUGUAUGUGACAAGGUCUUUAUUCGGAAGCGAUACCUUGCACGCCAUCGUAGAUGUCACACUGGUGAGAAACCUUACAAGUGUAAUGAGUGUGGCAAGUCCUUCAGUCAGAUGUCAUCCCUUACAUAUCAUCAUCGACUUCAUACUGGAGAGAAACCUUACAAAUGUGAAGAAUGUGACAAAGCUUUCAGACACAAUUCAGCCCUUCAAAGACAUAGGAGAAUUCAUACUGGAGAGAAACCACAUAAGUGUAAUGAGUGUGGCAAGACCUUUAGUCAGAAGUCAUACCUUGCAUGCCAUCGUAGCAUUCAUACUGGAAAGAAACCUUACGAAUGUGAAGAAUGUGACAAAGCUUUCAGUUUCAAAUCAAACCUUGAAAGUCAUAGGAUAACUCAUACUGGAGAGAAACCAUACAAGUGUAAUGAUUGUGGCAAGACCUUCAGUCAUAUGUCAACCCUUACAUGCCAUCGUAGACUUCAUACUGGAGAGAAACCUUACAAGUGUGAAGAAUGUGAUGAAGCUUUCCGUUUCAAAUCAAGUCUUGAAAGACAUAGGAGAAUUCAUAAUGGAGAGAAACUGUACAAAUGUAAUGAGUGUGGCAAGACCUUCAGUCAGGAGUUAUCCCUUACCUGCCAUUGUAGACUUCAUAGUGGAGAGAAACCUUGCAAGUGUGGAGAAUGUGACAAGGCUUACAGUUUCAAAUAAAAUCUUGAAAUACGUCAGAAAAUUCAUACUGGAGAGAAAUGUUAUAAGUGUAAUGAUUGUGGCAAGAUCUUCAGUCAUACGUCAUCCAUUGUAUACCAUCAUAAAUUUCAUAGUGGAGAGAAACCUUACAAAUGUGAAGAAUGUGAUGAAGCUUUCAGUUUCAAAUCAAACCUUGAAAGACAUAGGAGAAUUCACACUGGUGAGAAACCUUACAGGUGUAAUAGGUGUGGCAAGACCUUCAGUCAUACAUCAUCCCUUACAUGCCAUCAUAGACUUCAUACUGGAGAGAAACCUUACAAAUGUGAAGAAUGUGAUGAAACUUUCAGAUACAAAUCAAAUCUUGAAAGACAUAGGAGAAUUCAUAAUGGAGAGAAACCGUACAAGUGUAAUGAGUGUGGCAAGACCUUCAGUCAGAAGUCAUGCCUUACACGCCAUCAUAGACUUCAUACUGGAAAUAAAUCUUAUAAGUGUAAUGAGUGUGGCAAGACCUUCAGUAAGGAGUUAACACAUGCCAUCAUAGACGUCAUACUGGAGAGAAACCUUAGAAGUGCAAUGAGUGUGGCAAAACCUUUCAUAGGCAGUCAGCGCUUAUUUACCAUCAAGCAAUCCAUGGCAGAGGGAAACUUUACAAAUGUAAUGAUUGUCACCACGUCUUCAGUAAUGCUACAACUAUUGCAAAUCAUUGGAGAAUCCAUAAUAAAGAGAGACCUUACAAGUGUGAUAAAUGUGACAAAUUUUUCAGACAUCGUUCAUACCUUGCAGUUCACGGGCGAACUCAUGCUGGAGAGAAACCUUACAAAUGUGAAGAAUGUGAUAAAGCUUUCAGAUUCAAAUCAAACCUUGAAAGUCAUAGGAGAAUUCAUACUAGAGAGAAACCUUACAAGUGUAAUGAGUGUGGUAAGAUGUUCAGUCAAAAUUCGGCCCUUGUAAUUCAUAAGGCAAUUCAUACUGGAGAGAAACCUUACAAGUGUAAUGAAUGUGGCAAGGUUUUUAAUCGCAAAGCAAAGCUUGCAUGUCAUCAUAGACUUCAUACUGGAGAGAACGCUUGCAAGUGUAAUAAAUGUGGCGAGGUUUUUAAUCAACAAGCACACCUUGCACGUCAUCAUAGAACUCAUACUGGAGAGAAACAUUACAAGUGUAAUGAGUGUGGCAAGACCUACUCUCACAAUUCAGUCCUUGUAAUUCAUAAGACAAUUCACACUGGGGAGAAACCUUACAAGUGUAAUGAGUGUGGCAAAACCUUCCAUCACAAUUCAGUCCUUGUAAUUCAUAAAACAAUUCAUACUGGAGAGAAACAAGCGUAAUGAAUGUGGCGAGGUUUUCAAUCAACAAGCACACGUUGCACGUCAUCAUAGAAUUCAUACUGGAGAGAAACCUUAGAAAUGUGAAGAAUGUGACAAAGUUUACAGUCGCAAAUCAAACCUCGAAAGACAGGAGAAUUCAUACUGGAGAGAAACCAUAAAAAUGUAAGAGUUUUUGACAAGGCUUUCGGACGUGAUUCACACCUGGCACAACAUCCCAGAGUUCACACUGGAGAGAAACCUUACAAGUGUAAUGAGUGUGUCAAAGCCUUUAGUGGGCAGUCAACACUUAUUCACCAUCAGGCAAUCCGUAGUGUAGGGAAACUUGACUAACGUAAUGAUUCUCACAACGUCUUCAGUAAUGCUACAACCAUUGUAAAUCACUGGAGAAGCCAUAAUGAAGAGAGAUCUUACAAAUGUAAUAAUUGUGGCAAAUUUUUCAGACAUCGUUCAUACAUUGCCGUUCAUUGGCGAACUCAUGCUGGAGAGAAAUCUUACAAUGUCAUGAUUGUGGCAAGGUCUUCAGUCAAGCUUCAUCUUUUGCAAAACAGGAGAAUUCAUACAGGAGAGAAACCUCACAAGUGUGAUGAUCGUGGCAAAGCCUUUACUUCACAUUCUCACCUCAUUAGACAUCAGAGAAUCCAUACUGGACAGAAAUCUUACAAAUGUCAUCAGUGUGGCAAGGUCUUCAGUCCGACUUCACUCCUUGCAGAAUAUCAGAAAAUUCAUUUUUCAGGUAAUUGUUCCCAAUGCAAUGAAUAUAGCAAACCAUCAAGCAUUGAUUGACAUUAGAGUCAGUUCAGCAUUGACUUGAGUUUGAGUUGACUUAACAUUGAGUUCAAGCCUUAAUUGACAUUAAAGUGUUUAUGUUAAGAGGACUGGGCUGUGUGGCAUGGCUCACGCCUGUAAUCCCAGCACUUUGGUAGGCCAAGGUGGGUAAAUCACUUGAGGUCAGGAGUUUGAGAUCAGCCUGGACAACAGACCUGAGCCACUUUUCCCAGCCUGUUUUUUGUUUCUUUAACAAAAACUGAUAGGGAUUUUUAUGGGUAUCGUAUUGAAUCUAGAUUACAUUGGGUUAUAUAAUCAUUUAACAUAUUAAUUUUUCCAAACCAUCAAUAUGGGUUGUGUCUCUAUAUAUGUUUUUAAUCAUUUUGAUCAAUUUUUGUUGAUUUCAAGGUACAAACGUCUCACCUUUUUACGUUUAUUCCUAAGUAUUUCUUAUUUUAAGUUCUCCAGCAAAUGGAAGUGUGUUAAAAUUUUCUUUUAAAAUUGUUUAUUAUUAAAAUAUGGAAAUUCAACUAAUUUUUGGUGCUGAUACUGUAUUGUGCAAAUCCACUGAAUAUGUUUGUUAGUUCCAGUACUAUUUUGGUUGAGUCUGUGAUUUUCUACACAGAAGGUCAUGUCGUCUACAAACAAAUGUAAUUUUACUUCUUUCUUUCUGAUUUGGAUGAGUUUGAUUUCUUUUGCUAUUUAAUUGCUCUGGCUAGGACAGGCAGUAUUGAUUGAAUAGAAGGGGUGAGAGCAUUCUUGCAUCAUGUGAGAUCGUACAGGAAAGCAUUCCAUUUUCCCUGCUUGGUUAUUUACUCAUUUGUCAUUUCAUGGAUGUUCUUUCUAUUGUUGAGGUAAAUUUCCUUUUCUAUUUUGUUUAGGAUUUCUAUGAUGACUGGAUUUUGAAUUUUGUGGAACGCUUUUUCUCCAUCUACUAAGGUGAUGUGGUUUUAAUCUUUCAUUCUGUUCUAGUGGUAUAUAACAUUGAUUUGCUUGAAUAUGUUGAACCAUCCUUGCAUCCCAGAAAUAACUGGCACUUGAAUAUCUACAUUUUUUUAAUAUCCUCUUGAAUACAGUUUUCUAGGACAAGGGAUCUUCAAGAAGUUCUGGAAAAAUACAUAUUAUGAGAAAAUUGUGCAUGAAUUUCACAAUUUUUGCACCAAAAUAAACUAGUGCUAGUCUGUUAUAACAUGUCUGAACAGGCUCUAGUUUGAUGCCCUCAAAAGGAUAAGACAUGAGUAUAAAAAGAGACUCCAUCAAAGCAAUAUAAAUUCUGAUGAAAUUUAAACAAGAAGAAACAUUAAAUUUAUGAUGAGACCAGAUGCAGUGGCUCAGGCCUGUAAUCCCAGCAUUUUCAGAGGCUGAGACAGGUGGGCCACAUGAGCCCAGGUAUUCAAGACCAGCCUGGGAAACGUGGGGAAAUCCCCUUUUCUACAAAAAAUACAAAAAUUAGCUGGGCAUGGUGGCACAUGCCUGCCGUCUCAGUUAUUGUGAAGUCUGUGCAGGGAGGAUGGCAUGAACCUGGGAGGUCAAGAUUGCAGUGAGCUAUGAUCAUGCCACUGCACUCCAGCAUGGGUGAUGGAGAGAGAUACUGUCUUAAAAAAAGAAUACUUGUGGUAACGUUUGGGUAGAGGAAUAAUGAAAUCAUUGAUGCUUUAUAAAAAGGUUAUGGGGACAAUGCCCAAAAGAAAUAAACAGUUUGUAAACGGAUAACUUAUUUUGAGUUAGGGCAAGACAAUGUUGACAGUGAUGCAUGAAGCAGCAGGCAGACCUUCCACAUCAUUUUUACAGAAAAAAAAAUUAAUCUUGUUCAUGCUGCAAUGAAGAGGACUGACAGCAAACAGCAGAAACAUAGUCAGAAUUUAGAGAACAGCCUGGUUAACAUGGUGAAACACCAUCUCUAGUAAAAAUACAAAAAUUAGCUCAGCAUGGUGGCAUGCGCCUGUAAUCCCAGCUACUCAGGAGGCUGAGGCAGGGGAAUCUCUUGAACCCAGGAGGUGGAGGAUGCAGUGAACUGAGAUGGCAACAUUACACUCUAGCCUGAGCAACAAGAGCAAAACUCCAUCUCAAAAAAAAAAAAAUUGUCAAGUUCCUUCUCUUCCAUUCUUUGCCAUCGUGGUGUGUGCUUGACUCUGCUUCUUGCCACAUCUUCUCAGAAGACUUUCAGGAUUAAGCGAUUCCUGGCCAAGAAACAAAAGCAAAACCAUCCCACUCCCCUGUGGAUUCAGAUCAAAACUGGUAAUAAAAUCAGGUACGACUCCAAAAGGAGACAUUGGAGAAGAACCAAGCUGGGUCUAUAAGGAAUUGCAUGUGAGAUGGCACACAUAUUUAUGCUGUCUGAGCAUCACAAUCACGUUACCAUAUCAAGCUGAAAAUGUCACCACUAUCUGGACAGUUGGACAUGUUUUAUUGGGAAUAUGUUUUUUCUCUGUAAAUUUGUUAUAAACGCAUUGGUUGGCUGUGUUCAGUAAUAAACGUGAGACUUUUCAUUUCAAAACAAAA